AGACUUGUCUCCGGCCAGUCGCGCGUGGGUAGAGGCCUUAGGCGGGCGUUGCGAAGGGUUGUUUGCUAGAGUUCGGACCUUGUUACGGCGCGAAGUUCCCUCCUUGGGGCGGGGGAAAGGUACCGCACCCGCUACCUAGUGUGAAUGAACUGUGGCGUGGGCUGCUAAGGGCAGGCUGCGGAGUACCCGGGCCGUGGCCAUGAACUCACCCGUGGACCCUGGCGCUAGGCAGGCGUUGAGGAAGAAGCCACCCGAGCGGACUCCCGAGGACUUAAAUACUAUUUAUUCUUAUCUUCAUGGAAUGGAAAUAUUAUCAAAUCUCAGGGAACAUCAGCUUAGAUUAAUGUCUGCAAGAGCACGCUAUGAGAGAUACAGUGGCAAUCAGGUUCUCUUUUGUUCAGAAACGAUUGCCAGAUGUUGGUAUAUCCUACUUUCUGGAUCUGUGCUUGUGAAAGGCUCCAUGGUCUUGCCUCCUUGCAGUUUUGGUAAGCAGUUUGGAGGAAAAAGAGGAUGUGAUUGUCUUGUAUUAGAGCCUUCAGAAAUGAUUGUGGUAGAGAAUGCCAAAGAUAAUGAAGAUAGUAUUCUACAAAGAGAAAUUCCUGCCAGACAAUCCCGAAGAAGAUUUCGGAAAAUUAACUAUAAAGGAGAGCGCCAAACCAUUACUGAUGAUGUGGAGGUUAACAGCUAUCUUUCUCUUCCAGCUGAUCUUACCAAGAUGCAUCUCACAGAAAACCCUCAUCCACAGGUGACUCAUGUGUCUUCUAGUCAGUCUGGUUGUAGCAUUGCCAGUGACUCUGGAAGCAGCAGUUUAUCUGAUAUCUAUCAGGCUACGGAGAGUGAGGUAGGAGAUGUAGAUUUGACACGUCUUCCAGAAGGACCUGUUGAUUCUGAGGAUGACGAAGAGGAAGAUGAAGAGAUUGAUCGAACAGAUCCAUUGCAGGGGCGAGAUCUUGUUCGAGAAUGUCUUGAAAAAGAACCUGCAGACAAAACUGAUGAUGACAUUGAACAAUUGCUGGAGUUUAUGCACCAGCUCCCUGCAUUUGCAAACAUGACCAUGUCUGUAAGGAGAGAACUCUGCUCAGUGAUGAUUUUUGAAGUGGUAGAGCAGGCUGGAGCUAUUAUUCUUGAAGAUGGGCAAGAGCUUGACUCAUGGUAUGUUAUUUUAAACGGCACUGUGGAAAUCAGUCAUCCAGAUGGAAAAGUUGAAAAUUUGUUUAUGGGAAAUAGUUUUGGAAUUACUCCCACUCUGGAUAAGCAGUACAUGCAUGGAAUUGUCAGGACUAAAGUAGAUGAUUGUCAGUUUGUCUGCAUAGCCCAGCAAGAUUAUUGGAGAAUUUUAAACCAUGUGGAAAAAAAUACCCAUAAAGUUGAGGAAGAGGGAGAAAUUGUUAUGGUACAUGAGCAUCGGGAACUAGACCGGAGUGGAACCAGGAAAGGACACAUUGUGAUCAAGGCAACACCUGAGCGUCUCAUAAUGCAUUUAAUAGAAGAACAUUCCAUCGUGGAUCCAACUUAUAUAGAAGAUUUUCUAUUAACUUACAGGACAUUUCUUGAAAGUCCUUUGGAUGUUGGGAUCAAACUAUUGGAAUGGUUUAAGAUCGACAGCUUAAGAGAUAAGGUGACACGGAUUGUAUUAUUAUGGGUAAAUAAUCAUUUUAAUGAUUUUGAAGGUGACCCUGCUAUGACUCGAUUUCUAGAGGAAUUUGAAAAAAAUCUGGAAGAUACAAAGAUGAAUGGUCAUCUCCGGUUAUUGAAUAUUGCCUGUGCUGCAAAGGCUAAGUGGAGACAGGUUGUGCUGCAAAAGGCUUCCCGCGAGUCCCCUCUACAAUUCAGCCUUAAUGGAGGGAGUGAGAAGGGAUUUGGUAUUUUUGUUGAAGGAGUAGAACCUGGUAGCAAAGCUGCUGAUUCAGGACUGAAACGUGGUGAUCAGAUUAUGGAAGUAAAUGGACAAAACUUUGAGAAUAUUACAUUUAUGAAAGCCGUUGAAAUUUUGAGGAAUAAUACUCAUCUUGCACUUACUGUGAAGACCAACAUUUUUGUGUUCAAAGAGUUACUUUUUAGGACUGAACAAGAGAAAUCUGGUGUUCCUCAUAUUCCCAAAAUUGCUGAAAAAAAAAGUAAUCGCCAUUCUAUCCAGCAUGUGCCAGGAGAUAUUGAACAGACAUCACAGGAGAAAGGAAGUAAGAAAGUUAAAGCAAAUACUGUUUCAGGUGGAAGAAACAAAAUCAGGAAGAUUUUGGAUAAAACACGAUUUAGUAUCUUGCCUCCAAAGCUAUUUAGUGAUGGAGGCCUAAGCCAAUCACAAGAUGACAGCAUUGUGGGAACAAGGCACUGUAGGCAUAGUCUGGCUAUAAUGCCCAUCCCUGGAACACUCUCAUCCAGCAGCCCUGAUCUCCUGCAGCCUACCACCAGUAUGUUGGAUUUUUCCAAUCCUUCAGAUAUCCCUGAUCAAGUUAUAAGAGUUUUCAAAGUGGAUCAGCAAAGUUGCUACAUUAUCAUCAGUAAAGACACCACAGCUAAAGAAGUAGUUUUUCAUGCUGUUCAUGAAUUUGGUUUGACCGGUGCAUCCGACACAUAUUCUCUCUGUGAAGUUUCUGUUACUCCUGAGGGUGUCAUAAAACAGAGAAGACUUCCAGAUCAGUUCUCCAAAUUAGCUGAUAGAAUUCAACUCAAUGGAAGGUAUUACUUAAAAAAUAACAUGGAAACAGAAACCUUAUGUUCAGAUGAAGAUGCUCAAGAACUAGUUAAGGAAAGCCAGCUAUCCAUGCUGCAGCUCAGUACCAUUGAGGUGGCCACCCAGCUGUCAAUGAGGGACUUUGAUUUGUUUCGUAAUAUUGAACCGACUGAGUACAUCGAUGACCUUUUUAAGUUAAAUUCCAAAACAGGAAAUACUCAUUUGAAGAGGUUUGAGGACAUUGUAAACCAAGAGACAUUCUGGGUUGCCUCAGAAAUUUUAACUGAAGCAAAUCAGCUCAAACGAAUGAAGAUUAUUAAGCAUUUUAUUAAAAUUGCACUUCAUUGUCGAGAAUGUAAGAACUUCAAUUCCAUGUUUGCAAUAAUAAGUGGCUUGAACCUGGCAUCUGUAGCAAGACUCAGAGGAACUUGGGAAAAGUUACCAAGCAAAUACGAGAAACAUCUUCAAGAUCUACAAGACAUUUUUGAUCCAUCUAGAAACAUGGCAAAGUAUAGAAAUAUUCUUAGUAGUCAAAGUAUGCAGCCUCCAAUUAUUCCACUCUUCCCUGUUGUCAAGAAAGAUAUGACAUUUCUACAUGAAGGAAAUGACUCCAAAGUAGAUGGUUUAGUAAACUUUGAGAAGUUAAGAAUGAUUUCCAAGGAAAUCCGCCAAGUUGUUCGAAUGACUUCUGCUAACAUGGACCCAGCUAUGAUGUUUCGACAGAGGAAGAAGAGGUGGCGGAGUCUGGGGUCACUGAGUCAAGGAAGCACAAAUUCAAACAUGCUGGAUGUUCAGGGAGGUGCUCACAAAAAAAGGGCACGCCGCAGCUCUCUGCUUAAUGCCAAGAAGCUAUAUGAGGAUGCCCAAAUGGCAAGGAAGGUGAAGCAGUAUCUUUCCAGUCUCGAUGUAGAGACAGAUGAGGAGAAGUUCCAGAUGAUGUCAUUACAGUGGGAGCCUGCAUAUGGUACCUUGACCAAGAAUUUAAGUGAGAAAAGAUCAGCCAAAUCAUCUGAAAUGUCUCCAGUGCCUAUGAGGUCAGCUGGCCAAACAACUAAAGCCCACUUGCAUCAACCCCACAGAGUAAGCCAGGUGCUUCAGGUGCCAGCUGUUAAUUUGCACCCCAUCAGGAAGAAGGGACAAACAAAAGACCCUGCACUGAAUACAAGUUUACCUCAGAAAGUUUUAGGAACAACUGAAGAAAUAAGUGGUAAGAAGCAUACAGAAGACACUAUUUCUGUGGCGUCAUCUUUACAUUCUAGUCCUCCUGCAUCUCCUCAAGGCUCCCCUCACAAAGGUUACACACUUAUUCCAUCAGCUAAAUCUGACAACUUGUCUGACUCCAGCCAUAGUGAGAUUUCUUCACGGUCCAGCAUCGUGAGCAAUUGUUCUGUUGACUCCAUGUCUGCAGCUCUACAGGAUGAACGGUGUUCCUCUCAGGCCCUGGCAGUCCCUGAAUCCACUGGGGCAUUGGAAAAGACAGAGCACGCUUCAGGGAUAGGAGAUCAUAGUCAACAUGGCCCUGGGUGGACACUCUUGAAGCCAUCUCUAAUCAAGUGUUUAGCUGUCUCAUCGUCUGUGAGCAAUGAAGAGAUUUCUCAAGAGCAUAUCAUUAUAGAAGCAGCUGACAGUGGUCGUGGAAGUUGGACUUCGUGUUCAAGCAGCUCCCAUGACAACUUCCAAAGCCUUCCAAACCCAAAAAGCUGGGAUUUUUUGAACUCUUACAGACAUACCCAUUUGGAUGACCCCAUUGCUGAAGUUGAACCCACUGACUCUGAGCCCUAUUCCUGUUCUAAAAGCUGCUCUAGAACUUGUGGGCAGUGUAAAGGAAGCCUAGAGAGAAAGAGUUGGACCUCCUCCAGUUCUCUGUCUGACACGUAUGAACCAAACUAUGGGACAGUUAAACAGAGAGUAUUGGAGAGCACCCCAGCUGAGUCAUCUGAAGGCUUGGACCCCAAGGAUGCCACUGACCCAGUUUAUAAAACUGUCACUUCAAGUACAGAAAAGGGCUUGAUUGUGUACUGUGUCACCUCACCCAAGAAGGACGAUAGGUAUAGGGAGCCACCUCCCACUCCUCCAGGAUAUUUGGGGAUUUCUUUAGCGGACCUAAAGGAAGGACCCCACACACACCUAAAACCUCCAGAUUAUAGUGUGGCAGUGCAGAGGUCAAAGAUGAUGCAUAACAGCCUCUCUAGACUGCCACCAGCUUCUCUCAGUAGCAACCUCGUGGCCUGUGUUCCAUCGAAGAUUGUAACUCAGCCUCAGAGGCAUAAUUUGCAGCCAUUCCAUCCUAAACUAGGAGAUGUGACUGAUGCAGAUAGCGAAGCAGAUGAAAAUGAACAAGUUUCAGCAGUCUAGCCUUUGGAUGACCUAUUUGAAAACCACUGAAAGUCGUGGAGGAAUGGGCAAGAACCACCUCAUGAUUCUGCAGGCCAUUGCUAACGAACAGCUCAUUGCUACAACCAGUCCAGAGGUUUUAUUCCCUCUACUCCGAGCAAUGAAAUAGACCUGAGUUAUGCUUCCUUUCAUUUAAUUUCUGCAGAUAAAUAGUUUCCUGAGCAAUGGAUGCUAUGCCUGGAUACCAGUCUCCACUUUGCACGCCGGAACUGCCUUGGGACCACAGUUACAGAAAAAAUGUAAACUCAGAGUGAUCCUUGUGUAUAUUGCUAUAGAUUUUUCUUUAACAAGCUAUUUUAAAGAUAAUGGCAUUAUUAUUUCCAAGCCAUAGCUUGGGCUGAAGGACAAAUUGAAAUUGUCUGCCAAUACCAAGGAUAUUCUUGUAUAUUUGAAAAAUAACUUAUUAUUUGAAUUGUUGUGGUUUUGUUUGUAUUUGAGAGCUCUUGUUAGCUGAUAUUCAUGUUUGAGGUCAUAAAAUUGUCUCUGGUCUGACCAAACAGAAGUCAUCUUUACAGAGGUGAUAUGCUUGAUCUACACAGAGAUGUGACUUGAUCUGUAGCACCAAUGCAAUGUAGGUCUCAGUUUGAGAGAAAUAGGAAGCCCUUUGCAGUUGAGGUGUUAGGAACCUGCUGGUCAUGGUGUGGAAGGCCAAAUGAAGCUGCCACAGGGUUUCUUGUCAGUCCUUUGGGAAAUGGGAGGGAGUAGUUUGGGGAGGAGGGUGGGAACCCUAAUUUCCACAGAAUGAAAUUUUGAUGUUAAAUGACAUGUAUACAAAUUCUUCCUUAAGUGAAAGUUAUGCUGCAUCGAAUUGUAACUGAAAGUAUAGAUCCAACAAAUAGAGACUGGGUUCUAGAGAGUUCUGGUCUAUAGAAACCCAAAACUAAAAUCUCUCAUAACUCAAGUAUGGAAUACUUUUUUUAAAGAAAUUCUUAUCAUGGGUGUUGUAAUAAUGAAGACGAAUUUGACUUUAUGCAGUGUUCUGCAGCAUGCCUCCCCCACAUCUCAUAGCACCAGGUUGUGUCUGACCUGACAUACCCUGCAGCUCUCAGCUGGCUGCAGUAACAUUUUGUGGGAGAAAGAGGAGCUGGAGUUACAGAAAUGAUUGUCUCUUGGUUCUCAGUUUUUAGCCCUUGAGAGGACAUACUUUUCCAGCCUCAUGGGUAUGGCACUCUUAAUUAAAAUUUCAGUGACUGUUUACUGGAUGAGGCAGAUUUUUCACAUUUUUGCAAAUUAAAUAUAUUUUAUAUAUAUUAAGUUUAAUUUUUUCAGUUUUUUUAAUGUAAAAGCAAGUGAAAUUUUAAUAAACUUCUGUAAUUACCAAAAAAAAAAAAAAAAAAAAAGCCAAAGCCAUUAACGUGCACUACCCAGAUCAACUUGGAGCCAAAAGGGGUUUACUUCUGAAUGGCUGUCCGUAUGUGUCCACAUAGGAUUUAGUUGGUUUGUGGCCUCCUUUAUAGAAAUGUGUUGUCUUUCCCUAGCUGUCUCUGCUGUCUGUCUUCCUGCAUAUCCCCCUUCAUUUUAAAAUCAUGAAUCAGUUGUAAGUGGUAAAUGGUAGUAGUUCAUCUUUCCCAUCAACAUGAUUGUCUCUUUAUUUUAGGAAUAAUAGCAUUUCAAAAAUUCCUGUGGUAAAGAAACAUUAAUCUGAAACUUAAGCCUUAGAAAUUAAUCGCAGGUAUGAUAGAAUGAGGCUUGGUGGUUCCAUAGCUUUCUUGGUCCUUUGAAAUGGGAAAUAACCUGAACCAAAAAUCCUAGUUUGAAAGUUACACUUCAGUGAUUUGGCCUAUAAACAGUGGUCCUAUGAUUAUACAUUUUUUCCUUCACUGAUUUGCAUAAUUUUGUUUUCAUGGCCACAGCAAAACAAUGUGAAAUAUAUUUUUGCUAUACCCACUUUUUUUAUCAAAUUCAGAUGUCUACUCUCACCAUUUUAUAUUCAUUUCCCCAGAAAAAUGUGCUGUUUUCAUAAUGUCUUUAUUUAGCAGGUCUUUCAAACCAAAUGGAAGCCUUACCUGUCUUUGUCCUUAAUAGUGUAAAUAUCUUGCACAGAGUGUUGAGGCCUAUGGUUUUGGACUUGCACCUUACAGCUGCCUUUGUUUUAUCUAUCUAGCUUUAACUGUGAGUGUUCAGAUCAGCUGAUCACAUUGAUCAGGAGCCAAAGCCAAAUGCUUUGUAGUUUGUUAUGUAUGUAUCCCUUAAAAAAUCAUGAGGUUUUGAUUUUUAUAUUUUAACUAAGGGUACAUUCCUGCCUUCUCUUAGUUUGUCAUAUGACUAGAACAAGAGAAGUCUUAAGCUGCAUUUACUCCAAUUCCAGAUCUCCAUUUGUUUUUGUUUUAUAAAUUUAUAAUCUUAAUGAAGAGACUAGUGCCCUCUCUUCCUGCCACAACUCUCAAUCUGCCAAGACUGUUGAAGCAGUUAACGCUCAGUGCAAACUUUUGCCAAAUAGUAAGUUUCAACAAAAUAUCUUUAUAGUGAAAGAUUUUGAGAAUUAGUAAAUCCAGUACAUGAUUCCAUAAAAGCUUAUUAAAGUUAAUAAUUCUAAUUUACUCCAAAUGAUUACUUUCAAUAUGAUCUUUGGGGAGAAAAAGCCUUUAGUGAAUUUUCUUGAGGGUGAUAAAUCACAUCAUUGCGAUCUAUAUCACCUCCUUGAGAAUCUCUCCCAGGCUGAAAAUGUGAUGGUAAUCAUGGGUGUUUUUAAGAACAAAUCUAAUUUUUAUCAAGUGUUCUUUCCUCUACAAAAAAGGAAGGAGGAGAAAAAGCUUCCUUAAAACUGAUUAUUUUGAUUCAAUUUUAAGUUUCUAAAAAAGGUGAUAUUAAAGUAUAUGUAUUCCUUCAGCAUUACCUUAAAGGCUAGAAAAACGGGAUAAAUCUUCAGAAAAGUGUCAAAAGUGUCACAGUACAUGUUCAAAUUUAAACUUGAAUCCUGGUUCAUCUUUGACUUUUGUUGUGCAUUUUUAAUGCUUCUUUAUUUUUGAUACACAGAAUGCAGUUGAACUUGAUCUUUUAAAAUUGAGACAUGUAAGCUAAUCAGCAAAAGACAGAAACAAAACUGCACAUCUGUAAUAAUCAGAUAGCAAUUCUACUGCACAAUUCAUUGAUUGUAAGGUAUCCUGUAACAAGCAAUGUUUGUCUCCUAUUUUUUGAUACCUCUUAAACUUAUGUCUUUUAGAAAGACAGUGCCUCUGUAUGCUUUUUGUAUUUUUACUGAGUGUAAAUAUUUGUUAUAUUUUUGGUUAAGAGAAUGUAAAAAUACCAUUUAUUAUUAUCAUAUCUACUAAUACAUUGGUGGAAUCAAUAAAGAAUCUACAUUAA